AUCCCACAUGGCGGCGCUCCUGAGGAGACUGCUGCAGCGCGAGAGGCCUUCGGCGGCCUCUGGCCGCCCCGUAGGACGGCGCGAGGCCAACCUGGGCACUGAUGCCGGGGUUGCGGUGCGAGUGCGGUUCGCUCCCAGCCCCACAGGUAACCCUGGCGGACGUGACGCUACAGGCCGAGGCCCCCUGUCCCGUCUCCGCCCCACGAAUGUUCCCGAAUGAAUCCUUUCCGGUGGUGUCAGAGUGGGCGGGCGGAGGAGGGUUAAGGCAGCGCGAGCCCAUUUUACAGAGGCGGAAACUGAGGUGCAGGAGCGGAAAUAAUUCAAAUUGCCAGGAGUUUCUUGUGUUUUUUGUGCCAUCCCAUCUCUUUCGAUCUUUUUUUCAUGCAUUCCAUACAUGUGCAUUGAUGACAACCUGUGUAACAGGUGUUGUAGACGCUGGGAUACAGUGAUCAUUGAGAAAGGCUUCUUGCACCUGGGUGGCCUCCGCACUGCCUUGUACAACUACAUCUUUGCUAAGAAGUACCAGGGGAGCUUCAUCCUGAGGCUAGAGGACACAGAUCAGACUCGCGUUGUGCCUGGGGCAGCGGAGAAUAUUGAGGACAUGCUGGAGUGGGCAGGCAUCCCGCCUGAUGAGAGCCCCCGCCGGGGCGGUCCUGCUGGGCCCUACCAGCAAUCUCAGCGGUUGGAGCUGUAUGCCCAGGCCACAGAAGCGCUGCUGAAGACCGGAGCUGCUUACCCCUGUUUCUGCUCACCCCAGCGGCUGGAGCUCCUGAAGAAGGAGGCCUUGCGGAACCACCAGACGCCCCGGUAUGACAAUCGGUGCAGGAACAUGAGCCAGGAGCAGGUGGCCCAGAAGCUGGCCAAGGACCCCAAGCCUGCGAUCCGCUUCCGCCUGGAGCAGGUGGUGCCAGCCUUCCAGGACCUGGUCUAUGGCUGGAAUAGGCAUGAAGUGGCCAGCGUGGAGGGAGACCCAGUCAUCAUGAAGAGCGACGGCUUCCCCACAUACCACCUGGCCUGCGUGGUGGACGACCACCACAUGGGCAUCAGCCACGUGCUGCGAGGCUCUGAGUGGCUCGUCUCCACUGCCAAGCACCUGCUCCUCUACCAGGCCCUGGGCUGGCAGCCACCCCACUUCGCCCACCUGCCCCUGCUCCUCAACAGGGAUGGCAGCAAGCUCUCCAAGAGGCAAGGGGACGUUUUCCUGGAGCACUUUGCUGCUGAUGGCUUCCUGCCCGAUUCCUUGUUGGACAUCAUCACCAACUGUGGCUCAGGUUUUGCAGAGAACCAAAUGGGCAGGACCCUGCCGGAGCUGAUCACACAGUUCAACCUGACACAGGUCACCUGUCACUCAGCCCUGCUGGACCUGGAGAAGCUCCCAGAAUUCAACAGACUGCACCUCCAGCGGCUGGUGAGCAAUGAGAGCCAGAGGCGCCAGCUGGUGGGGAAGCUGCAGGUCCUUGUGGAGGAGGCCUUUGGUUGCCAGCUGCAAAACAGGGAUGUCCUCAACCCAGUCUACGUGGAGAGGAUCCUCCUGCUGAGACAGGGUCACAUUUGCCGCCUGCAGGACUUGGUGUCCCCAGUAUACUCUUACCUGUGGACUCGCCCUGCAGUAGGUCGAGCACAGCUGGACGCCAUCUCGGAGAAGGUGGAUGUGAUUGCCAAGCGUGUGCUGGGGCUUCUAGAAAGAUCUAGUAUGAGCUUAACUCAGGAUAUGCUGAAUGGAGAACUGAAGAAGCUAUCAGAAGGUCUGGAAGGCACCAAGUACAGUAAUGUGAUGAAACUCCUUCGGAUGGCCCUCAGUGGACAGCAGCAAGGACCUCCUGUAGCUGAGAUGAUGUUGGCCUUGGGACCAAAGGAAGUACGGGAACGGAUCCAGAAGGUGGUUUCCAGCUAGGGAGAGGAUGUUUCGGGCAGUGGAGAUCGCCCUAAGAACCUGUGAGCUUAGAAACAGCUUUCAGAGACCAGAAGGAGGCCUGGGGCCCGUCGGGAAGUUUGCUGAAGGAACUAAGAGUGGAAACAAUCUCUGACUGCACACAAGUGCAUUUGUGAUCCACCACAGGCACGUUUUUGUCAAUUGGCUGGGGAAGCCCAACCCAUCUAACCUCCUGGACUCUGGAAAGGCAUUCUCCGGGUCUGGUUUCUCACACAUUACACAGCAGAGGUUUGGAGUUAGUUCACAGAAAAGUUAACAUCCCGGAACAGUGCAGAAGGCUUGGGUUUCAGUUUGCUAGGGCCCCCAUAACAAAAUGCCACAGAACCAGGUGGUUUAAACAACAGAGAUUUAUUUUCUCACAUUUGGAGGCUAGAAGUUCAAGAUCAAGGUGUCAGCAGGCCUGGUUUUUCCUAGAGGCCUCUUUUGUUGGCUUGCAGACAGCUGUCUUCUCACUGUGUCCUUGUGCGGUCUUCCCUCCAUGCACACACAUCUCUAAGUUUCAUUAUGUGCCCAACGUUCCUCUUCUAAGAACACCAGUUGGACUGGAUUUUAACUUUAACCAGCCUCAUUUAAGUUAAUCACCUCUUUAAAUGCUCAAUCUCCAAGUACAGUCUCAUUCUGAGGUUCCAGGGGUUUCUCAACGUAAGAAUUUAGGGGGACAGAAUUCAGCCCGUAGCAGCUGGGCAGCAGGACUCAUGGGUCCCAGUUCUCAGGCCCCAAGGACUCAGAGCAGCAAAGGAUACGUGACACAAGCAGGGCUGAACUGGACACCAGACUUUCUUUGGGGUUGUAAAAGGAGAAGUGUGACUCCACUGCCAAGGGUAAGCACUCUUGUCUUAUGCUACCCUUUAUUCUUGAACCUUGGGGCAGCCUGUGUCUCCCUUCCCUAAACGUCAUCUGUUCCGUUUUUCCAGUCUUCCAGACCUGGUCCUUGGACUGGAGACCUUCACCCUUCCUAUUUUGUGGCUUUCUCUUCAAAUCCACCUCGUCCUUCCUCCAUGACUUAUAAGUCAUCAUCUCUGCUGGUUUCUGAAAUGAGAUAUGCUUCUUGGGGUCUUCAGUGAAGAGGAAUAGCAAGUGAAAGGAGGAUGGUGGCAGGGUACAUGAACCCCUACCAGGCUUCUAGGCUUCCCCUGCAUGGCAGCCAGCCUCUAAGUUGGCCCCCAACCAUCCCUGCCUUCUUCUAUUCACACCCUUGUGUGGUUCCUUCCCACAUUGAAUAGGCCUGACUUGUGUAACCACUACACUAUUGAAGAAAUGAGAGUUUGACUUCUGAGGGUAAGUCAUAAAAUACAUCGUGGCUUCUGUCUUGUUUUCUUUGAUCGCUUACUUUGGGGGAAGCCAGCUUCCAGGUCAUGAAAAUACUCAAGCAGCCUUAUGGAGUGCUCCACAUGACAAGGGAUCGAGGCCUCCCACCAAUAGCCAUGGGAGUGUGCAAUCUUGAAAGCUGGUCCUUCAAUUCCAGCCAAGCAUUCACAUGACCGCAAUCCUAGCUGAUCUCGCUUGUGACCUCUAUGGGAGACCCUAAGCCAGAACCACUCAGAGAAGCUGCUCCGGAACGUCAGACACACAUGAACUGUGAGAUAGUAAACGUUUAUUGUUUAAAGCUACUUGGUUUGGGGAUAAUUUGCGUUUCAGCAGUAGACAAUAUAUUUAUUUUGUCCAGGGGAGUGGAAAGGCGAUUACAGAGUUUGUUGAGCCCCAUAGAGUCCUAGUCUUUGCUUAAAGAAAUAUACCAGUUCUUUCUAAUACAGAAUCCAUUAAGUUCGUUGGUUGCAAACAAUAGAAACCAACUCUGCCUCACUUAUGUUUAUUGGAGGCCAUAAGAGAGCCACAGCAUCUACCAAAAAGCCAAAAAAAAAACAGGUUUUGGAAAAGACAGGAACUAGCUACAGGAGCUAAUGGCCAAUCUUGUCUGAGUUCUUUGAUGGCGACACAUGAACUACAGCCGUUUUGUUGUUGUUAAUUUCUCCGUGUUUUCCCCUCAGUUUUGGAUGACUCUGCUCAAGGUUCAGAUUCUGAGGAGCAAGUAUCUGUUGGGCUAUCUGAGGUCCUGCUACCAUUCCUUGGCCAGUAAUAGGUAGUUUCACAGGGAUUAUAUGCAAUGGAGGAAAAGUUGUUCUCAAGGAAAACUAGGGAGCUUUCUCCAGAAGAUGAUGUAAUGGCAGAAACAACAGGUGGUUGACCACAGAAGGGGACAAUAAUAAUACUUGUAAUUUAUUGUGCGCUUAUAUGAGCCUCACCCUCUCCCAGGUGUCAGAUAAUGCUCGUAAAUGCCUUAGUCCAUCAUCUCAGUAAAUUUUUUUUAUAACACUAUGAGAGAAGCAGUAUUUUUUUUUUCUGUUACAGAUAUGGAAACCGAGGUUCUGAAAAGUUAACUAAAACUUCCGAGGUUAUAGUACGAGGCAAAACCAAGAUUUAAACUCAGAUCUGUGCCGAUCCAGAGUCCAAGCUUAACUCUGAUCUACUGAGUGUUGUCAGAGCAUCUGUUUCUAAGACAUUAAGAAUGGUUAAAAGGAGCUUCUUGGCUCAUGGUCAAGUGAGUGUUUUUAACAAAGUGAGUGGUCAAAAUACUAAGUCGAUUCUGGUAUAUCUACAACAUGGAUGAACCUCUAGGACUUCAUGCUAAAUGAAAUGUCAGUCACAAAAGGACAAAUACGUCCUAAUGCUUUGUGAGGCAAAGGUGGUAGGCUUGUCAAAGGCCAGGAGUUUGGAGACCAGCCUGGGCAACAUAGUGAGAUCCUGUCUCUACAAAAAAUUUAAAAAUUAGCCAGGUGAGGUGACAUAUGCCUGUAGUCCCAGCUACUUGGGAGACUAAGGUAGGAGGAUCACUUGAGCUGAGGCGUUAAGGCUGCAGUGAGCUAUGAAUGCACUACUGCACUCUAACCUGGGCAACAGAGCAAGAUCCUGUGUCUAAAAAAAAAAAAAUGAAUAAAAUAAAGUUAAAAGGAUAGAUACUGUAAGAUUCUACUUAUUUGAAUUACUUAAAAUAAUCAAAAUUAUACAGGCAGAAAAUAAGAUGGUGGUUGUCAGACUUGGGGAGGCAGAAAUGGGAAGUUACUGUUUAGGGUAUAGAGUUUCAGUUUUGCAAGAUGUAGUUACAGGGGUCAAUGGUGGUGAUAAUUGCACAACAUUAUAAAGAUACGUAAUGCCGCUGAACUGUAUAUUUAAAAAUGACUGAGAUGGUAAAUUUUAUAUUUUUCUGUAUUUUACCACAGUUUUUAAAAAAUACUAAAUUAGAGCUGGGCCUGGUGGCUCACACCUAGAAUCCCAACAUUUUGGGAGGCCAAGGCAGGCAGAUCACUUGAGGCCGGGAGUUCAAGACCAGCCUGGCCAACAUGGUGAAACCCCAUCUCUACUAAAAGUACAAAAAUUAGCCAGGUGUGGUGGUACAUACCUAUAAUCCCAGCUACUUGGGUGGCUGAGGCACAGGAAUUACUUGAACCCCCACAGAACGGGAGGUUGCAGUGAGCCAAGAUCACACCAUUGUACUCCAGCCUGGGGAACAGAGCGACACUCUGUCUCAACAAGAAAUUAAUAAAAAAGCGAAAUUAAUAAAGCUGUUGCUACUUCCUCAA